CCGGAAAUUUGCGGGCGCGCCGGAAGUUGAGGGGAGUUUCCUGCGAGCUCGGCUUCCUCAACAUGGCUGCGCCCUUGUCAGUGGAGGUGGAGUUCGGAGGUGGUGCGGAGCUCCUGUUUGACGGUAUUAAGAAACAUCGAGUCACUUUGCCUGGACAGGAGGAACCCUGGGACAUCCGGAACCUGCUCAUCUGGAUCAAGAAGAAUUUGCUAAAAGAGCGGCCAGAGUUGUUCAUCCAGGGAGACAGCGUGUGAGUCCCACUCCUCCCUUCCCUGAAGCAGGUGGAGGGAGGGACGGAUAUUUGAGCCCCCACCCUCGGGUUCAGUCCUGGCCUUCUCUGAAUCCGGUUCUCCCCUUCCUCCUCCCUAACUCUUCCAGCUCUGAGAUCUGUUUUCAGUUUUCUUGUUACUAAACCGAACUCUUGAGGAUUUUUUAAAUCCCAGAUGAAAGGAGCCUGGUGAAUUUCUCAGAAAACUUGGAUUCUGCCCUCUGGUUGCCACAGACUUGCUGUGGGACCUUAGGCGACUUACUUCGCUUCUCUGGGCCUCAGUUACUCUCUACACAGAAAGUGCUGAGGAAAAAACGUAGCUAGUACAACUGAAGAGCUAAAUAUUCUGUUUUAUUUCAUUGUAAUUUAAAUAGCCACAUGCAGCUAGUAGAUUACCAUACAGUGCAGCACGGGUCUAGAAUUCCAAGGAGUCAUUGACUCUGUGCGUGCACACACCCAUGCACAUGCACACACACUCACUGGGGACACCCCAUAGAAGCCCAGUGCAGUCUCCUUGGAAAGGACCAGGUUCCAGUUGCCACGAAGUUACUUCUAAAACAAGGCCAGUCCCCCACGUGAAAGGUGGCCGGUGCAGUUGUGAGGCUCGCUUAUUUGCCUCGAAGCAUAGGUCACUGUCAGGUCCUAAGGGAUCAGGCCUAGGGGAUCAGCCCUCCUUCAGGUCAUGGUCCAGUGGUCCUGGAGGCCACCUCUAAGGCCAGCAGUGCUCCUUGGGCCAUUACCAGUGGGAGCCAGGCUAAGCUGCCUGACCAAAUGUUGACCUACCCUGCCUUAUGCCAGGCAGGACUGCACGUGAGCAUUGCCAUGUGGCAUGGCAACUGAUUCGGAAGAGGCAAAACAGCCUUCUCUCCAGGAUGGGCAUGCAGAGGCCUAAAAAAAAGCCGAAGUUCUUUUCCAGGGCUAACGAGAAUAAGAUUAGACCCCUGGAAAAGUCCUACUAAUGGUUACCAUGACAGUGUGGCAAGCACUCCACACAUAUCAGCUCAUUUCGUUUUCGUAUAGGCCUUGUGGGUUAGACAGUAUCACUUAUCCCAUUUUCAGAUGAGGAACCUGAUACUCAGAAACAAAAUGACCUGCCCAUGGUCUGGGUGGUGGUGCUGGCUGGCAUUUGCACCCAUUUUCCAUCUGGCUACAAAGACCAUGCAUGACUGACCUGGUUUCCUUCACACUCAGACCAGCCUCCCCUUCCUGGGAUAUCUUUAGCCAGACCCCAGGAGGAAGGCUCCUCAGCACACUCUCCUGCAGCCCAAAGCUCUCAGCCUCUCUUCCUCUGUGCUACUGCCUCCUGCCUCUCACUCCUUGCUACUCACCACCAUCUUUCCCACAGGCGGCCAGGAAUUCUGGUGCUGAUUAACGAUGCCGACUGGGAGCUACUGGUCAGUACCUUGGGGGACAUCCCUCCCCCAGCCCCUGCCCUUGCUGCUUCAGUGGGAAAGCGUUGGGCCUCUCCUCAGGCACAUAUAGAGUGGCUGGGUAAUCCUCCGCCCCACUCCAGCCCCACACUGAGGCUGCUGGAGUCUCCCACUCCAGGUGAGGAAGGGAUGGGUAGCUGGGGACAUGGGAGUACUCCUCCAUCCUGAAGAUUUGCAGGUUGAGGUAUAGGAUACCCAUUUUUCUGGUAGAGUCUGUCUCUUCCAGAGCAGCCAGUCCUCAGCCCCUGUUCUCCCAACUCCUGGGGUGGACCUGGGAAGGUGGCCCUGAGGGUCUCCCGCUCCCCUCUCUCCCGCACCAGGGUGAGCUGGACUACCAGCUUCAGGACCAGGACAGCGUCCUCUUCAUCUCCACUCUGCACGGCGGCUGAGGGCCCUUCUCUGGGCCUGGGCACCCUUAGAGGGGAGAACGAAGCAAUCAGACAUCCCCUUGGGCCCUGCUUCCAGGUCUCCCUGUCCCCCUUGCCUGCCUUCUUCCCUGCUCUGUCCCCUAAGCUCCCUCCAGGCAGGGAAAAGAGGCCAGGUGCUAAAAAUGAGCCUUUCUCAAGCACGUGAGCAGCGGAAGGCAGACAGGCGCCAGAGCCCAGCACUCCCUUUUCCAGCAGCUGUGGUGGGGGAGGGUUCCCCUCCAGUUUGUCAAGAGUUGAAGGAGGCUCUGUGGCCAGGUGACCUGGCUGCCUUCCACUCCUUGUACCUCAGUCUAAACAUGGAGUGGCCGCUGACAAGGCGCUCCAGCCCCAGAGCCAGCGUCUUCAUGGGGAAGAUGAAUGGACCUGAGUAGCUGAAGGAAGGCCCCUCCCUACCCAAAGACUGGAGGCUUCUCAGCCUCAAUUUCCCUGUCUGUACAGCUGAGGGCUCUGCCUGUCCCCCACUGCUAUCAGUAUGGAACCCCAGCUGGGGUCCCCUAUUGAGUGCCGACUCCCCCCACCGCCAGCAGCUGCUCCUCCAGCCACACCCCUCCUGCUCCCCCCACCCCUAGCCCUUGACCCUGGCUGGCCUGCCCCGCUCCACAGGCCACCAGAUGGGCUCCUGAGACCCUCCCCAGGCUGCUUACAGCUCAUUCUGCUGGGGGUAGAGAUGAGGGGAGGGAGUAAGUUAAACCUUGGACUAGCAAGUAGAAGCCUGGGGGGAUGCGUGUGCCUCAGUUUCCUCCUCCACAACUGAAUAUAGUGGCUGAAAACUGGGGAGAUACUUGAUGGCGCGAAUGUCCGUUUUCUCUCCCUUCCCACCUCCUGCAGGAAGCAGGACGGGGCAGGCAGCACCUGGUAGGCACAGUGCUUUGCCCCUCCUCCCCUUCCCUUCUGGAAGUCUUGGGGCCUCAGUGCUUGCAACAGCCGGCCUUGGGCAAAUAAAAGACUAGGUUGUUUACUAGCCUUGCUUGGAGCUUCAUCCUUGGAAACGGGUGGCACCUCAUAUCCCCCCAGCCGUGGUCUGUGAUACAACCUCUCCAUCCUCAGCCUAGGGCCUCAGAGCUACCCUUCACCCAAAAGAGGGGUGGGGGUGAACACUCAGACAAUCUGAGAGGGGGUAGUCUAAUAGAGCCAUCUGGAGAAGGGAGUGGCAGAGCCAGUCUGUGCUGACCAGUCUGUGUCCCGGGACGCAUCCCCACCCGUCUGUCCAAGGCUUUGUCCCACCAGCUGCAGCCAGCAGCCUCAGAACCCAAAAUGAGGGUAGCAUAGAUAAGACUGCUGAGCCCCCUUUCUGUGGUCUUUCCUUUCCAUGACCUAGAGAAAAGAGCUUUGCUGGAGGGAGACCCCCAAAAAGAAUUAGGGUGCUAACAUCCCACCAAAAGCAUCAUCCCACCCAAAAUGUUGCUUUUCAUUCUAUGUCAAUAAUUUAAGGUGGAAUUUCUCUCACCCUGUGGAGAUGAAAGUGGCAAAAGGUUGUCCCAGCAGUGUUGGGGGAUGGGGUGUGCACAUCAUUCUUUUGGGGGUAGAUGACCUGCUGGCUGGUGGGCUUUUCUCCAGGACUACUGCAGGUAGAGACCCUCUGGGCUUGUGUGGAGUGGGAGCAGCCGUGUUGGGACUAUGGGGAGGAGCUGGUCUGGGUGCAAAUUAAGGCCAGUGUUGGGGUCUGAGUGCUGUCCAGAAAGGCUGUGUGACCAACCCUCACUAGUUCCUGAGGUCAGGGUCUCCAUGUUAGGGAACAGAGCAAGAGACUUGGAACAGCUCCCUACAGCUGCACUUCUAGAAGGUCAGCCUGUCCGAUUCUUGUAACCUGGAGGUCCCUCCCCAUCUGCAGCCCCCUGAGCUGCAGGAGCGGCCCCAUCAGUGCACCUGAUUGGAACACACUAGAUUUCAGGUCCUGGAAACUGGGCGCUAGGAUCCGUUUCCCUGGCUGCAGAGAGUGGGAGGUGUGAUGUGGAAUAUCCCUUCUCCCAGCACACCCCAAUUAAUACUGAAGAGUAGGGCAGGAGGAGGUGCUGGGAAAACCGGGUUUCUUGGCACAUGGGGGUGCAAGCACUGUGGUUGAAAUUGGCCAUGUCCAAGGCACACCAGACGAUUUCAGGUCAUUUUUAGCCCUAGACUGGAAAGGGGUCAGGGGACAGGUGACCUGGGCUCAGCCCCCAGCAGCUCCCAACUGCCCCUCUCCCAAGCAACUCCUGAUCCCUGCUUUUGAGGAAAUAAACAAAUAAAACCCCGCUAUCUCCGAA